GCGGGAAGUGGAACCUGGCUCUGGGGAGAAGCCGCGUGAGAUCCGCGCGGGUGCUAGCUAGUCCUUUCUCGUCGCUGCUCGGCUCGCGGCCCGUGGGGUCGGCCCCGCCACCGUUGCCGCCAUGCCCAUGAAGGGCCGCUUCCCCAUCCGCCGCACCCUGCAAUAUCUGAGCCAGGGGAACGUGGUGUUCAAGGACUCCGUGAAGGUCAUGACAGUGAAUUACAACACGCAUGGGGAGCUGGGCGAGGGCGCCAGGAAGUUUGUGUUUUUCAACAUACCUCAGAUUCAAUACAAAAACCCUUGGGUGCAGAUCAUGAUGUUUAAGAACAUGACGCCGUCACCCUUCCUGCGAUUCUACUUAGAUUCUGGGGAGCAGGUCCUGGUGGAUGUGGAGACCAAGAGCAAUAAGGAGAUCAUGGAGCACAUCAGAAAAAUCUUGGGGAAGAAUGAGGAAACCCUCAGGGAAGAGGAGGAGGAGAAAAAGCAGCUUUCUCACCCAGCCAACUUCGGCCCUCGAAAGUACUGCCUGCGGGAGUGCAUCUGUGAAGUGGAAGGGCAGGUGCCCUGCCCCAGCCUGGUGCCAUUACCCAAGGAGAUGAGGGGGAAGUACAAAGCCGCUCUGAAAGCCGAUGCCCAGGACUAAGGCCCACGGUCACUGUGGGCUGGGGUGAUGGUGUCUGACCAGUGGGGAGAUUGGAAUGGGAUUACUUUGGCCCAGGGAAGCCCCUGGUUCUGUCCCUGGAGACUCUGGAAAUCCUUUUGCAUUAAAAGGACUUUACACACCUGUGUAAAAGGAUGUGGGAGAGGAGGGUCUGAAGCUGAGCUGCUAAAUGAAUAUCCCUGCUCUGCUGGUCAAUAAAACGCUUCCUAAUAGCAGCUUGGCGUGUAUCUGGUCCUAGUGAAGAGGAAGGCCUGUGUAGCAGAAAGGCUUUGGGCCUGAGAGGUUAAGGCCACAGCCUGUUGACACCUGUUUUGGUCCUGCGACCCUUUACUGGUCUCCGCUGGCUUUGAAUCUUCCUCUGGGCUCUACUCUGGAGAACAUAAGGGCUGCUGUGGUUGAGUCUGGCUAGCACUGUCUGUGGUUGGCAGUGUGUACACCCCUCCGUUCAGUUCCUUGGGGGUAUUUUUCAGAAAUCCAAAGGCAACCCUUCGUGCAGUGCUCACUUUUUUAAGUACAGUUGAUUACCCUUGCCUGCUGGGGGGCCUAGCCAUGGGCCAGAGAUGGAGGAGCCCCAGUGGCUGACAGGCCAGCCUCACUCAGGCACGUACCUGCUGACCAGUCAGCCACUGCCAACCCAUGGCCCAGCCACUGUGUGCAUUAGCAGGGAGGUUUGUAGGCCAUGGAGGAAAUGAGGAGACACCACCUAGUGGAGACAUUGGGGCCCUGCUGGGGGGAUGGUGUCUAUAGCUGGCUCUGCUGGCUCCCUCAGGCCCUGCUUACCAAGCUCUGGAGGAGGGAGUGCUGCAUUACUGAGCACCUUCCUUGUUCUUUCCUCAUAGGACACUGAUGUUACUGUCACUUUAGUUAUGCUAAAGUGGAGGUUUCAGCCUCCAGAAGACAGCAGAGCCUUCUAGGGUCACCUUAAGAAUAGGUUUAGCUAGGCUGGGUGUGGUGGCUCAUGCCUGUAAUCCCAGCACUUUGGGAGGCUGAUGUGGGCGGAUAGUUGAGCCCAGGAGUUCGAGACCAGCCUGGGCAACAUGGCAAGACCUUGUCUCUACAAAAAGUACAAAAAUUAGAUGGGUGUGGUGUUUCGCGUCUGUAGUCCCAGCUAUUUGGGAAGCUGAGGUGGGAGGAUCUCGAGCCUGCGAGAUCAAGGCUGCAGUGAAUCAUGAUCGUGCGCUACUGCACUCCAGCCUGGGCCACAGAGCAAGACUGUCUCAAGAAAAAAAAUUUUUUAAAUAAGUUUAAUUAUAAAGUGAAGGACCAGUUGGACCACGGACCCCUAGAAACUCAGCCAAGGAGACCUGACUUUAUCUGAGACAGGAAGGCAGUGGUUAAAAGAAUUAAAAAAGGACAGUGGUGCUUGACAGAGCAGGACUGAAGUUUUCAUUCCUCUACCUGCUGGGGCCUUGGUCAAGUCCUAAAAGCUUUCCAGGUCUGUAACUGGUUUUGUCUGUAAAAUGGGGAAAAGGUUACCUUUUCUGCCACAUGAAGUAGCUGGCUGGUGAAAUGAUGUCAUACUACGAUGUGUUUCAUUAACUGUUGGAGAUUAUCACAUUAAAUUGAGCAGAUUUGGAUCUUUUACAUUUGAUGCUCAAGUUUGAUUCUGUACCAGAUCUGGGUUUGGGGUGAUGGCUUGUCGGGGGUGGGAGGGGAAGGUGGGCAGAGACUGAUGUAUAAUGGACAGGUGUUCCUUGAGUGACAGACUUACAAAGGGAGUGUUUAAUUGAAAUCUAGCAUCUUGUCUCUCUGCUAUCAGCAUUUUGGCUGGGUGGAAAAAGCUCUCCUCCACAGAGAGCCCUCCCAUGUCUGCUGGUUUCAGUUCCCCACCCAACUGACUGAAGUCUUGACCUUGAUACCACCUGCCUGGGCGUUCUACUUGGCUGCAAGGGCUCUUCAGAAAGCACCUAGUUCCUUUUGGCUUUCAUCUGCAGUGUAGGUCUCCAUAGCUAGUGACACACAAAGCCUUAUGAGAGUAUUCCUUCCCUCUAGGGCCCAAAGAGGCUGCUAACCAGCAGGAAUGUCCUGAACCAAAAGGAGUGGUGACCAUUCUCUAGACAGAAUAAAUGUCUGGUCCCUAAUGGGACAGAUAACUAGGGUUUGAGUUCAGGCUUGACACAGGAGCAAUGGGCAGUGAGGUGGACAGCCCAGACCCUGAAAGGACGUGUGGAGACAGCAGCAGUCCUGUGGUGCAGUUACUGCCUGUGUGGCCAGCUUCACAGGCAGCAGAUAAUUUGUGGAAAUAAACAUUAUUUUCUUUUUUUGUUCCCUGUAGGCUACUUGAUCCUGGAUAGUUUCUCUUUAAACCUUUGUCUUUCCCUAUUUUGUUUAGUAGUGAUGAAAGAUGGGUUUAAAAUAUACAGAAAUGGGAGAAAAUUAAUUAGAGAAAAUGUGAGGAUUUUAUAAUUGAUAACAUGUUCUUAAUUUUACUUGCACAAGCAGUGUUCACAGCCUUAUUCUGAAGUGACCACUUUUCUUCUCUUUGAGGCACUACCUGGCAGCACCAUCUAAACCUGUAUCAUCUGCUGUGGUCCCAGUUACUCAGGAGGCUGAGGCAGGAGGAUCACUUGAGCCCAGGAGGUUGAGGCUGGAGUGAGCCAUGACUGUACCACUGCAUUCCAGCCUGGGUGACGGAGUGAGGCCCUAUCUGCCUGCCAGUGAGUUCUGUCAUGCAUCAGACUUUGGACCUCAGAAUUUUCACCUGGAACAUGAGAGGUCAGAUGACAUAAUGAAUAUGUUCUAACUUCUGAAACUUUUGGAGCUUGUUUUUGCCCUUGAUAGCACGUAUCCUUAGAGAAUAAGCUUGCCAAUUUAAGGCCUGUCUGUAAUGGCAUCUGAAUGUUCCAGCAGCCUAACUGUGCUCUGCUCCAGAAACAUGUGUGUGGCUUCCCUACCUCCACACCAAGGAGCUGCCUUGCUGGGUGGAUGUAAAGACUGUCCUGCCAGGGUUUCCCACUAAAGGUAUUAAUAAGUCCAGUGGACCACAGAGGGCCCAAUCCCUCUUGGCCGCUAAGGCUAAGGUAGGAGCCAGAGAGCUGUAGAGACAGGACCACCAGGAUGCUUCAUGUCCAUAACACAAGAGAGCGCUGCAUUGUUUGGGGGCCAGGCAUUACUACUAUCAUGAAGAAAAAUGAAGAGCAGGAUGCAUGUUAGUCUUUAAUUCACUUUUAAUAGUAUAAACCUCAUUUAGGUAGUAGUAUUAAGCCACAACAAUAAUGCCACAUUGAAACAGCAUUUAAUAAAAUGCAUAAAGCUAAUUCAUGCACUGCAAUACUCUAUAUACAAACACAACAAUGCAAAUUCUUCUUCAAGACUGAAGACAUUGAUUAGAUAUAAAAUUCAGUUUAAAAAGAACAUGCUAUUUUUUAAAUGCCAUCACAUAAACAAAGUGAUUUCACAGGGAGAAGAAAGCUGUAUAAAGCUGCAGCUUUCAACAGGUUUUAAACCUGGCAUUAAAAUGUAAUGGCAAAACCAAUAUUUUCUAUAUUGUGAAGGGCAAAGGUUACAGAAACGGUCCCAAGAAAAUCUAACACCCAAAUUUUCCUUUGAUAGAUAGAUGCCUUUAAAAGGGCUGGUAAUGCAGUUACAUUCUAACAGAGAAGUCCAAACUACAGGUAAAAACUACGGCUUGUACUGUGAAAAAUGUGCAGCUUUUCAGUUAUAAAACUAGUUGAACACUGGUUUACAAGAUAAUCCGUAGAACAGAGAGACUGUAGAAAAAUAUUCCAGCACUUGAGUUGUGUGUGGCAGCAGCAUUUGAGUCCAUGAAUGCUAUGGUCAUUAAAAUAAUUGAUUAUACUUUCCUAAAGAAAAGCCAUUUUUUAAUGCAAAGUCUACUACUUCCAAAUGUUAUUCCAAACAUUAAAUUUUAACAGUCUAUCAAUCAAUAAAUGUUGAACAUUUUUUUUCUA